UGUUGAAUGUGUUAGGUUUUUAAAGUUCUUUACCUUUUAACAGGAUGAUCCACAUUCAUUUCCCUUUAGGUCCUUUUUGCAAAUGUUUUGUGGCCAUCCUCUGGAUUCUCACAUUGUUUUUGUGCUUUGGAACUCAAAGGGGUAAUUCAGCUAGGUCUAACCAGUGCUGAAUAAAGAUGGAUUACUUUUUUUUUUUUUGAAACAGAGUCUCACUCUGUCACCCAGGCUGGAGUGCAAUGGCAUGAUCUCGUCUCACUGCAACCUCCACCUCCUGAGUUCGAGUGAUUGUCAUGGCUAAGCCUCCUGAGUAGCUGGGACUACAGGCAUGCGCCACUACGCCUGGCUGAUUUUUUUGUUGUUGUAUUUUUAGUAGAGACGGGGUUUCACCAUGUUGGCCAGGCUGGUCUUGAACUCCUGACCUCAGAUGAUCUGCUUGCUUCAGCCUCCCAUCGUGUUGAGAUUACAGGCCUGAGCCAUCGUGCCAGGCCACUUUUUUUUGAGACAGUAGCCACUUUUUUUUGAGACAGUAUCUUGUUUUGUUGCCUGGGCUGGAGUGCAGUGGCAUGAUAGCAGCUCACUGCAGUCUCAACCUCUGGGGCUCAAUCCAUUGAUCCUCCCACCUCAGCCUUCCAAGUAGCUGGGACAACAGGCACGUGCCACCACGCCCAGCUGAUUUUUAAAAUUUUUAGUAGAAACUAGGUCUCACUGUGUUGCCCAGGCUGGUCUUGAAUGCCUGAGCUCAAGCAUUCCUCCUGUUUCGGCCUCCUGGAGUGCUAGGAUUACAAGAAUAAGCCAAUGUGCCCAGCCUUUUUUUUUUUUUUUUUAAGAGACAGGGUCUUGCUCUGUCGCCCAGGCUGGAGUGCAGUGGCAUGAUCUCGGCUCACUGCAACCUCCAGCCCCUGGGUUCAAGCUAUUCUUCUGCCUCAGCCUCACGAGUAGCUGGGAUUACAGGCGCCCACCACCACGUCUGGCUAAUUUUUUUUUUUUAAGUAGAGACAGGGUUUCACCAUGUUGGCCAGGUUGGUCUCGAACUCCUGACCUCAAGUGAUCCACCCGCCUCGGCCUCCUAAAGUGCUGGGAUUACAGGCGUGAGCCACCUUGCCUGGCCUCCCUUAGUAUUUGAUGAUACAGAAAAAAUUUCGGUUAAAAUGGAAUGCCUUGUGUAAUUCAAGGGGAAAUCUAAAGUGCAUCAGAAUUUGCCCUGAAAGAGUGAGAUGUGUGUGAGUCUCAAAUUCUGCCUACUCUCCUCCCCUUACAGAGGGUUGGGUUGUAUUUGCAGCCCUUAUUUGAGCGCUAAAAAGGUUAUCACGCCCAUGUGCUCACUUCAGCAGCACAUAUACCAAAAGGUUAUUGUGCUUGUUAUAUGUUGGACAGUGUUCUUUCAGAUCACAAAUCUUGUUUUUAUCACUGUUAAAUUGAGGGUGUUUUUCAGGUAGAAGCAAAAAUACUUGCUGAAAUGUGAUUUAUAUGUGGAACCCACCUUCAAACCAACUUGCUGAAGUUAUGACUGCCUAUAAUCCAUUAGGAUGUAUCAGGACAAACUGGCUUCUCUCAAGAGGCAGUUGCAACAACUGCAAGAAGGUACAUUACAGGAAUAUCAGAAGAGAAUGAAAAAACUAGAUCAGCAGUACAAAGAGAGGAUACGGAAUGCAGAACUCUUCCUCCAGCUGGAAACUGAACAAGUGGAACGAAAUUACAUUAAAGAAAAGAAGGCAGCAGUGAAAGAAUUUGAAGACAAGAAGGUUGAGCUGAAAGAGAACCUGAUUGCUGAGCUAGAAGAAAAGAAGAAAAUGAUUGAAAAUGAAAAGCUGACAAUGGAACUGACUGGAGAUUCUAUGGAGGUGAAACCUAUCAUGACCAGAAAGUUGCGGAGGCGACCAAAUGAUCCCGUCCCCAUCCCAGACAAGAGGAGGAAACCUGCUCCAGCCCAGCUAAACUAUUUGUUAACAGAUGAACAGAUCAUGGAGGAUCUGAGAACAUUAAAUAAGCUUAAGUCACCCAAGAGACCAGCAUCUCCAUCCUCUCCUGAGCACUUGCCUGCAACACCCGCGGAAUCUCCAGCCCAGAGGUUCGAAGCUCGGAUAGAAGAUGGCAAACUGUACUAUGACAAAAGAUGGUACCACAAGAGCCAGGCCAUCUAUCUGGAGUCAAAGGACAACCAGAAACUGAGCUGCGUGAUCAGUUCUGUAGGAGCCAAUGAGAUCUGGGUGAGGAAGACAAGUGACAGCACCAAGAUGAGGAUCUACCUGGGCCAGCUUCAGCGCGGGCUCUUCGUGAUCCGCCGGCGCUCAGCUGCUUGACUUUCUACAGUGCUCUUCUCUUGACCCUUUUUCUGGAGUGGGUUUUAUUUUUGUUUUGUUUCGUUUUCUCCUUAAUAGAAAAAUGUUAACUUACUGGGAAUAGCUACUCAGCCUUGGAAAUGGAGAGCACUGCAGUGAAUUCUUUAGGGCACUUUUGUGGCCGGAUGCUUCCAACUUUGUCAGUCUUUUCUGCCUCAACUUCUUCCAGACAUCAGUCACCAUGAGACUGUUUUACUUUCAGGCGUAUUGGGGGGUUUGAUUUACUUUCCUUUUAUUUCUUUAUUUUUUGCUUAUACUUGUUUUUGAAAACCUCCUCUGAGUUUGAAGGGACAGCUAUUUUUAUUGAUUAUCUUUAAGUCUCUCUACCAUGGAGAAGAGCAGGAAGGGAUACACUCUCCAGUGCAUUUUCAUGUUUUGAAUCUGAUUAGUGGAUCACGUAGCUACUUUCCCUGUCGCGUCCAAUUCACUAUUUGCCCAGAAGCUUGGGGCAGAGGUCCUAGCAGGAGAUGAUGAAUUCUCGUGGCUCUCGGCCUUCUCAGAGAAAUAAAUGCUUUGUGUAACAUCUGUGCACACCAUCCAUUCCGCUCGCUGAGCGAUGGAAAAGCUUGCCUGGAAGACUAUGUGCACUGAAGUAAAUGGGGUUGGGGGAGGGGACAUUUCAUAUUUAUAAUGUGCUGAAGGUACCAUAUUUUAAAUGUUAUUUAAUGCAGGUGAUUUAUUCAAACAUUUGUUCUAGCUUAAGCUGGAAUAAGCAGUGGUCAUUUCAGAAGUUUUCAUUUGUAAUUCCUUCCUCUCCCUUGUUCCCAAGUAGGUAGUAGUAAGUAUGUGCCACAGGCUGAUUAUCUGGGUAAUCUUUUACGGGUGGGAGGUGAGAUUGAUAGUGCAAUAAUCAGUGAUCUAUAGACCCUCAUGCACGAUUCAAGUUUCACUCUUGUGGCUGAUGCCAUUAUUGCACAUUGGCCAUUCCAAACCUGUGGAGAACUUUGUUGUCAGGCCCUGAGCGCUCACAGCUUCAUUUGGCCCAGGUUGAAGACAAGGAAAGCUCUGCUGUGGCUGCCUCUGGACUGACACCCUCCCUAAUGAGUCCUGAUGAAACAGCCUUUCCUACAUCCUUCCCUCACUCCCAUGAUUGGAGAAAUGAUUCAUUGGGUGAUGAGUGUUGGGGUUUUCUAUACUCAUGUUGCCAUCUUGAGAUGUUCAAAAAAUUUGGGGUUAGAGCAACUGUUAGCGUCUCUAUGAGCAAUCAGUAGAACUUACACAUCCUAGGAAAUCUUUCUUUGUAAGUAAUUCUUUUGGUCUCAAGUGAUUCUCUUCAUGUUGUCUCUUGAUGUACAUACCCCCAAGCAAGUUGGGGGGACUGUGAUGACAAUUAAAUCACCUUCUCUGAAGUUCUGGCUCUGCAGAGACCAAACCUUACUGACUUGUACAGACUUGUACAAGUAAAGACUUAUACAGAUAGAUUUUUGUUUUAACUUACAAUCCGUUUUUUCCUCUUUUUUUUUUUUUUUUCUGGUGUUGGAGUCUUAUUUAGAAAACAGGAUAAAUGACGCUGUUAUCAAAAGUUGCCUGGGGUUCUGUAUUUCUUCUCUGCCCUCCAAUCCCCGACUGCUAUGAUGUUUACUACAGUGAACCCAGCCCAUGGUAAACACAGGCUUCACCUGUUCUUGUUUGUUAGCCUUGACUGUGAGGCAGGACUUCCCUCGCUUGAACUGUUACACAUACGAUGUGUGUGUCACAUCACAUAUUGUGCAGCUGUUGGUUUUCAUGUAGUGCCCUGCGAUGGAAAUUAGAUAUAUUUCAUGUAUUUUUCCAUUGAAGGUGGAGUUUUUCAAUGAUCAUGUGUUUUGUCCUCCUAAACAGUAUACCAAAGUUUGUUUUUAUAGUUGAGGAUUGUAUUGAUAACCACUGGGGUUCCGCAUUGAAGCAGGAACAAAUUGCCUCUUUUUCUGGCCUUCUCUGUGGGACCUCUGCUUUUGUGAAGCAACUAUUUAUUUGAAGACCAGGGUAUGGGCACUUUUGCCUUCUCUCCUCUCUGACUUUUGAGGGUAUUGAGGGCGCCCUUAGUCAUAGUCUCGACUCCGCCAUUGCCUUCUCCUCGGCGUCCUCACAACUCUUAAUUGGGCCUAGUGAAAAUGGGGGCAGGUGAGAAGUCCAUUUUGAGAAUCAGCAUAGUAAAUUACAUUUCUAAUCCCAGAGGACUUAAUAUUUUCUUUUGUCACCCCAGAGGUGAAAAAUCAGCAGUUGAAGCCUGACAGGCCUCAGUGGUGACCAGGAACAGAAGCAGCCUUCCUGUUAGUAGAUGGGGGUACUUCUGUGGUGGGCAGAAGCCUUACUAAAGGGGAAGACAGACUUUGAAGUUUCUAGACGAGAAGGAGGCUAGCUUCUAGCCUGGGUGGCCAUUAUUCCAAAAGGUCAUUGUUUCUCACUAGACCCCAGGGCACCAGAUGAAUUUCCAAGUUUAAACUCUUUCCUGCAGGUGAUUACUUUGAAAAAGGUUGGUCCAGACCAUUUUGAUCAAGAACCUGUAUAUGUGUUGUGUUAGAGGCAUCUGCCUCAAGUCUAUGUACAGUGUUUGCUGCGGGUGUGUUCCAAUAUUCAUUUUACCUCUGCUUGGGGGUUUUGUGUGUUCCCCUCCCCCCAUGCCCUGCCUACCCCCUUUUCCCUGAACCACGUCCUUUUGAAUAAUUUCCAGAUGGAUUUCUGUAGCCAUACCAAAGCCAGGGUGUUUUCAUUCAUGCGGAUACUAGUAUUUAUAGAUGUCUGACUACCUAACUUAAUUUUUGUUUUUGAACUUCUAAUUGGGGCCAGUGUAAGGUCGAUCCCAGAGGCUGAUCUGCAAAUCAAGCUACAUGUAUUUGUGUAUAAGACCCUGUGUUCAGGACUGGGUGACUUUUCUAAGAAAUAUGGGGUUUAGAAUGGGGUUGACUGUAUUUUUUAACCUAAUUCUGGAGAGAAGAUUGUAUUUUUUACAGUUUUUUGGGUUUGGCUUCCUUCUCACAUUUCUUUAGCUUUGAAUUUUUACUAAAUAAAUUUCCUCCUGAUUAAUUUUUUUUUUCUCAUCUGGGAAUUUGAAAUCUCGGUGCUUACUGUUACACCAAUUUGUCCAAAGAGUUGAAAUCACUUUAAUGCCAGAACAUGGUAAAUUUGCAGCCAUUUCAAGCAGGUGAUGGUCUUUUUUUAUAACAUCGUUAACGGGUACCAUUAAAUAUUCUGAGAGGUGAAUGUAAAAUAUAAAAGGUAUAGGUUUUUUUUUUUUUUUAAAGAAAACAAUAAACUUUCAAAGAGAAAACCAGCAUGAAGUCUGUAUUGUAUCCAUUGACUUGAUAAGUGAUAGAAAUUUAUUUUAGGUUUUUGAUCCAUUGCUUAUGGGGAAAGGAAGUUAGGGCAGAGGAAGGGAUAUUCUAGACAUUUAAUUCUUAGUGAAGACUAAGAUACAGAAUGAUGUCAGGCUAAUACUCAGUUUUGUAAAGAGCAAUCUGGGGUGUUGACCCUUAAAUGUUUGUGCACUCUUCUUGUUGCAGAUAAAAGUCAUUAAAAAUCAAGUGAAUAGAAUGGAUCUUGGGUGGAAAAACAAUCUUGAAAUAAACUUGUGAUUGAGGA